ACUCACUUUCUGACUUAGGCCACAGGUCGUUUUACCAUGUCUGGACGUGGCAAGCAGGGCGGCAAGGCUCGCGCCAAGGCCAAAACCCGCUCCUCUAGAGCUGGGCUCCAAUUUCCUGUAGGACGAGUGCACCGCCUGCUCCGCAAGGGCAACUACGCUGAGCGGGUCGGGGCCGGCGCGCCGGUUUACCUGGCGGCGGUGCUGGAGUACCUAACUGCCGAGAUCCUGGAGCUGGCGGGCAACGCAGCCCGCGACAACAAAAAGACCCGCAUCAUCCCGCGCCACUUGCAGCUGGCCAUCCGCAACGACGAGGAGCUCAACAAGCUGCUUGGUAAAGUUACCAUCGCUCAGGGCGGUGUUCUGCCUAACAUCCAGGCCGUACUGCUCCCCAAGAAGACUGAGAGCCACCACAAAGCUAAGGGCAAGUAAGGGCUGAACUUUAAAAAUGUAAACUUACAAGACAAAAGGCUCUUUUCAGAGCCACCCA